GAGACGCAGAGGCGGACAAGAUGGCGGCGGCAGCUGUACAGGGCGGGAGAAGCGGUGGUAGCGGAGGCUGUAGUGGGGCUGGUGGUGCUUCCAACUGCGGGACAGGAAGUGGCCGUAGCGGCUUGUUGGAUAAGUGGAAGAUAGAUGAUAAGCCUGUAAAAAUUGACAAGUGGGAUGGAUCAGCUGUGAAAAACUCUUUGGAUGAUUCUGCCAAAAAGGUACUUCUGGAAAAAUACAAAUAUGUGGAGAAUUUUGGUCUAAUUGAUGGUCGCCUCACCAUCUGUACAAUCUCCUGUUUCUUUGCCAUAGUGGCUUUGAUUUGGGAUUAUAUGCACCCCUUUCCAGAGUCCAAACCCGUUUUGGCUUUGUGUGUCAUAUCCUAUUUUGUGAUGAUGGGGAUUCUGACCAUUUAUACCUCAUAUAAGGAGAAGAGCAUCUUUCUCGUGGCCCACAGGAAAGAUCCUACAGGAAUGGAUCCUGAUGAUAUUUGGCAGCUGUCCUCCAGUCUUAAAAGGUUUGAUGACAAAUACACCUUGAAGCUGACCUUCAUCAGUGGGAGAACAAAGCAGCAGCGGGAAGCCGAGUUCACAAAGUCCAUUGCUAAGUUUUUUGACCACAGUGGGACACUGGUCAUGGAUGCAUAUGAGCCUGAAAUAUCCAGGCUCCAUGACAGUCUUGCCAUAGAAAGAAAAAUAAAGUAGCCAAUUCUAAAAGUAGCCCUCUUUCUCCUGGAUCUUGCUGAAUUAGUGGCUUGGGGGGUGGGGGAGAUAAAAAGAACUUAAAAUGGGUAAAGUAAGAAAUGUUAAAAAGUCCCUGUUUUGUCCUGAAAUUUUAGUCUAUUCUGGGUAAAUAGGAUUUUCUGACACAGAUAUGAGAAGUUGUAGCUCUGAUGUCUAGCUGUAGUCUCCUUGAUCUGCUGAUUGCAUUAUUUUAAUUUGCUUUUCUGGGAAAGCAGUUUUGCUAAAAGCUGUACAGACUUUUUCUUUUGUACCUAGCAGUACUUUAUAUAGUAUAGCUUUGGGCCAUGUAGCAUUUUAAGACUCAAUUUUAAAAAAUUAUUAAUCUGUUGCUGACUCUUAAUUCCUAUUUCAAUAUGUGUUUCCUUGAAGAAUUCAGGAUACAACUUCUUGUGUAUGACAGCUUUCCUUCACACACUAUUUUUGUGGGUGUGUAUAUAUCUGAUUUGGGAAGAAUUUAAAAAACACAUAGCUUUUUAAUUUGUUUGAAACAGACUUUCUGCCUGUUACAUUUUUGCUUUUAACCAAUUAAAGAAGCCAAUGGCAUUUUAGUUUUAUAUUGUGUUUUCCACUAGUAUAUCCCUGUUGAUUUGUUUGUGCCUUUUAUUAACUGCCAUUUUCUAAAAUUUUUUUCAAUAAAAGGAAGGAAGAUGUGAAAAAAAUGGAGUCAUAGUUUUGAUGGAGAGAACAGAGAAACAAGUGUUAACAUCUUUCUACUAUAGGUUUUUUUCAUUUUUAGGCUAUUUUACUUGUCAAAGGCCCCUGAGAACCUGUAGCUAAGGAACUCUUAGCUUUCCAGUGAUAAUAACAAUAAUAACAACAUUCUGUACUUACUUUGUGCCAGAAAUGCUCCAAGUACUUUACAUGUGUUAAUAAUGCUCACAGCAAUCCUAAGAGGCAGGUGCUGUUAUUAUCCCCAUUUUACACAUGAGGAAACUGAGAUACAAAAGUUAAAUAAUUGUCACACAGCUAGUGAUAGAACUGGGAUUCAAACCUGGGGAGUCCGGCUUCAGAGUUUGUGGUCCUGCAGAGACAAAACAGCCGCUUUUCCAGUAUUUUCCCAGUAUGGUCAGAGAAGACCUGGGUGCUUGCCAAGAUCCUUUGACCUUUAGGAAUAUUUCCCUACAGCCUUACAAAACAUCAAUUUUGGCUGAGCCUAGUACCCAACACUAUAUUCAGUUUGUAAGAAAUUACCAUUAUCACAUUUCCUGUUUGUCUUGGAGAGGUUGUCCUAUCUCGCACCACAUGGUAGGGAAUUGUGAACAACACUGGACAGAAAGUUAAAGCCUUGGAUUCUGUACUCUUCAUUCCUGUAAACCUUGGGUAAGUUUCGGAAUUCUCUGUGAGCUUCUUAAAGUUUUUGAAAGCAUGUAACCGGAUAAGUGUAUUUUUACAAUGGAGGAGUUACAGUCAUCUUGGUAUUUGUGGGAGAUUGGUUCCAGGAUCCCCAAGCAUACCAAAAUCCAAGGAUGCUCAAGUCCCUUAUAUAAAAUGGUAUAGCAUUUGCAUAUAACCUACACACAUCCUCCCAUAUACUUUUAAUCACCUCUGGAUUACCUAUAAUACCUAAUAUAAUGUAAAUGCUAUGUAAAUAGUUAUACUGCAUUGGUUUUUUAAUUUAUAUUUUUUGUUAUUUUUUAAAAUAUAUUUUUAAUCCAUGGUUGGUUAAAUCUGUAGAUAUAGAGGGCCAACUGUACUGUUAGACACAAGGGUCUCGAGGCUUGCAGAUAGAGACUGAAUAACCCUCUCCAUGAUGAUCCCUUAGAGUUCCCCCACUGUGCCUUUUUCUUUACAUGUGCAUGCAAACAUGUGUCUCCACAUACAUUUUUUUUAACAAAAAUUGAAUUAUGUUGAUAUAUGUCCUGUAAUUUGUGUUUUAAACUUAAUAUAUCUUAGGCAUUUUCCCUGUGUGUGUGUAUAAUGCAGCUAUUAAAAAUGAGUCUGAGGCCAGGCA